ACUCCUGAGAGCAGAGCUGGCCGCAGCCAUGACCCCGCAGCUUCUCCUGGCCCUUGUCCUCUGGGCCAGCUGCCCGCCCUGCAGUGGAAGGAAAGGGCCCCCAGCAGCUCUGACACUGCCCCGGGUGCAAUGCCGAGCCUCUCGGUACCCGAUCGCCGUGGAUUGCUCCUGGACCCUGCCGCCUGCUCCAAACUCCACCAGCCCCGUGUCCUUCAUUGCCACGUACAGGCUCGGCAUGGCUGCCCGGGGCCACAGCUGGCCCUGCCUGCAGCAGACGCCAACGUCCACCAGCUGCACCAUCACGGAUGUCCAGCUGUUCUCCAUGGCUCCCUACGUGCUCAAUGUCACCGCCGUCCACCCCUGGGGCUCCAGCAGCAGCUUCGUGCCUUUCAUAACAGAGCACAUCAUCAAGCCCGACCCUCCAGAAGGCGUGCGCCUAAGCCCCCUCGCUGAGCGCCAGCUACAGGUGCAGUGGGAGCCUCCCGGGUCCUGGCCCUUCCCAGAGAUCUUCUCACUGAAGUACUGGAUCCGUUACAAGCGUCAGGGAGCUGCGCGCUUCCACCGGGUGGGGCCCAUUGAAGCCACGUCCUUCAUCCUCAGGGCUGUGCGGCCCCGAGCCAGGUACUACGUCCAAGUGGCGGCUCAGGACCUCACAGACUACGGGGAACUGAGUGACUGGAGUCUCCCCGCCACUGCCACAAUGAGCCUGGGCAAGUAGCAAGGGCUUCCCGCUGCCUCCAGACAGCACCUGGGUCCUCGCCACCCUAAGCCCCGGGACACCUGUUGGAGGGCGGAUGGGAUCUGCCUAGCCUGGGCUGGAGUCCUUGCUUUGCUGCUGCUGAGCUGCCGGGCAACCUCAGAUGACCGACUUUUCCCUUUGAGCCUCAGUUUCUCUAGCUGAGAAAUGGAGAUGUACUACUCUCUCCUUUACCUUUACCUUUACCACAGUGCAGGGCUGACUGAACUGUCACUGUGAGAUAUUUUUUAUUGUUUAAUUAGAAAAGAAUUGUUGUUGGGCUGGGCGCAGUGGAUCGCACCUGUAAUCCCAGUCACUGGGAAGCCGACGUGGGAGGGUAGCUUGAGGCCAGGAGCUCGAAACCAGUCCGGGCCACACAGCAAGACCCCAUCUCUAAAAAAUUAAUAUAAAUAUAAAAUAAA